AGUUUCACCCAGCAAGCGUGAGAACAGGUACUGCUUCCUGAGCACCGCCAGCCACCGGCACCAAGACCGGCCACAUCCCAGCACUGCCCACCUCUGCUCCCAGCCGCCAGAUGACGGAGGCUCUCGCCAGACCCUCAGCACGCAGAGCUGGCUUCUGAUAGAAGUGAUCGGGAAAGAAAGCAAAGCGGGAGGUGCCUCUUUAGAAACCACGAAGUGCACGCGGCGUCGACAGUGAUCACGCCACCUGGACAGCCAGAGUCCAAGGCAUAAGGAGGAAAAUGAGUCUCCUCAAAGAGCGGAAGCCAAAAAAGCCACAUUACAUCCCCAGGCCUCCAGGAAAGCCCUUCAAGUAUAAAUGUUUCCAAUGUCCCUUUACUUGCAAUGAGAAGUCACAUCUUUUUAAUCACAUGAAGUAUGGUCUUUGUAAAAACUCGAUUACUUUAGUAUCAGAGCAGGAUCGAGUUCCCAAGUGCCCUAAAUCUAACUCACUAGACCCCAAGCAAACCAACCAGCCCGAUGCCACGGCGAAGCCAGCCUCUUCCAAGUCUGUCGCAAAUGGACUCUCUGCCUUCGACUCGAAGCUUCAGCACAGCUCUGCCAGGGAAGACAUCAAGGAAAACCUGGAGCUGCAAGCCCGGGGAACCCACAGGUGCCUGGGACAGAAGCCAGCCCUCCACAGGGCAUCACCCUGCAAGAGCCCAGCUCCGGAAGCCGCCCUCGGUGCCCAGCCUGCUCUGGAAGGCGCAGCUCGGCCUUCUGCAUUUGUUCCAGUCGGCGAGCACAGACUCAAGGGGCCAGACAACGCCGAGGCGCCCGAGACACUGGCUUUACACAACCCCACUGCCAAGGCCGUGUCUUUCCACACCAAGUCGGCCUUCCACACUCCUGGCUACCCCUGGAAAGCCGGCUCACCUUUCCUUCCACCAGAGUUUCCACAUAAAAUCUCAUCUACAAAGGGGCUUGGGGCCAUUUCCCCUUACAUGCACCCCACAAUCCCAGAGUACCCGCCUCACUUUUACACAGAGCACGGGCUGGCCACCAUCUACUCGCCUUACCUGCUGGCUGGGAGCUCGCCUGAGUGUGACGCACCCCUGCUGUCAGUCUACGGAACCCAAGACCCGAGACACUUCCUGCCUCACCCGGGGCCGAUCCCUAAGCACCUGGCUCCAUCUCCAGCCACAUACGAUCACUACAGGUUUUUCCAGCAAUAUCCCUCUAACCUGCCGAUUCCUUACGGAUUUUACAGGCCAGAGUCUGCAUUUUCCUCCUAUGGUCUCAGACUCCCACCUGUCACUGGCCUCACCCGAGAUCAGAGCUCUCACCUGCUUGAAGAAGCCACCCUGGUCUAUCCAGCCUCGAGUCCUUCCAGGUUAAACCCUUCGGACCCCAACAGAAAACACGUCGAGUUCGAAAGUCCAAUUCCUGAGGCUAAAGACUCCUCCAAGGCUGGGCAGAGAGACACGGAAGGGUCCAAAAUGAGCCCCCGCGCAGGGAGUGCAGCCACGGGCUCCCCAGGGAGGCCGAGCCCCACCGACUUCAUGCAGACGAGCCAGACCUGCGAAGGCCUGUACGACCUCUCCAACAAGGCAGCCUCCAGCGCACUGGGAAGACUCUACCCGCCAGAGCAAAGCCUCACAGCCUUCAGGCCUGUUAAGAAAAGCACAGAAUGCCUACCUGCCCAGGCUGCUGAGACCACAGCAGAGUCUCCAGUAAGCCUCAAUGUUGUGAACGGAGACCCUCCUGCUCCGACCGGAAGCGCCUCUCUCGUCUCGGAGGCCGCGCCUUCCAGUCCGGACGACAGCUCCGGGAUGGGCCCCCUCAACCUCUCCAAGAAAUCAGAGAUAAACCUGGCAGCCACCCACGAACCCACGUACCAAGGCAGCCCCCAGGCGGAAACCGCCAGCUUCUCAGAGCUGCAGGACCUUCCACUCAAUCUCUCGGUGAAGGACCCCUGUAACACCCAGGCUCCGAGGCCUGCCUUCCCCGGUCGACCACGAGCUGCAGAACCUGCUGCUGCUGUUCCACAGAAGACUGGGACAGAAGGUUCUGAGGAUGGGCCCAGCCACCCUGAGACCAAGCCAGGCAGCCUCGACGGUGACGGGGCCCCACCCACAGGCCCCGGCGAGGAGGCUCCAGACGCAUGCGCGGUGGACAGCAGCGAGGAGCAGAAGCAGACGGCAGCCGUGGCCCUGUGCCAGCUGGCGGCCUACAGCCCCAGGAACAUCCGGGUGGGCGAUGGGGAUGCUGCGGCCCCGGAACCUGCCUGCCGGCAAGACACACCCACACUGAGCUCCAUGGAGAGCCAAGAGGCCCAGUGUGACCUCAGACCCAAAGGACAAAAGAGGACAAGUCUAAGGGAUGCUGGAAAAUCCCAGCAAGGAGCUAAGAAGGCGAAGCUGCAGGACACGGCCAGAGUGUUCACACUACGAAGGAGGGCCCGGGUGUCCUAACGCCGGGUUCACACGUGUGUUCACAGAGCUACGGCCACACACACGCCUUCCAAGGUGGCAAGCUACAACACCUCUGAACUGGCACUUUCACAUUUUUACAAAUGCAGCUGCUGCUUCUCAAAAAAACAAACAAACAAACAAACAAAAAACCCUCCAAUUCAGUUUUUAUAAAUAUUAAGCAUGAAUAUUAAAAGGUGCUUCUACUUUUGGUUGUAAAAACACCUGAAUGACUCUAAGACUGAUAUGUAUUUUCAAGUCUAAGCUGUCUUACAGAAGAUCUUUUAUAAAUGUUUCCUUAUAAAUAUCUCACCAUUACAACAAAUUGUUUUAACUGUUUUUCUAUUAGCUCUAGCUGCAUAUUUGAUGUAAAUGACAAUUACUGAAAAAAUGUCAGAAAAAACAUUUUCAGUACUAACAUUAAAGUGCCAUAUGUAAAAAAGAAAAAUGUGAUUUGUAUAACUAAAUAACACACAAACAUCAAGAGGCUAUUUAUACAAAUAAUUUAUUUCCACUAGGGAAAGUGCAUUACUGGUGAAGGUAUUAUCAAUUUAUUCUACUUGCUUAUAAUGUUACAGUGAAUGUUCUGGCUUACUCUGCCUCACUUUCCAUUCCCCAAAAUGAUGUGUAUGUUGCUAAUUUUCCAAUAAACUCAUAUGAACCAUAAGGAAACAUAAAAUGCAAAUAAACAUAAAUCUAUGUUAUCCUUUA